GUCUGCCGGGCCAUGGUGGCGCUGAAGGGUGUCCCCGCACUGCUGUCCCCCGAGCUGCUCUACGCGCUGGCGCGGAUGGGGCACGGGGACGAGAUCGUUCUUGCGGACUUGAACUUCCCGGCCUCCUCCAUCUGCCAGUGUGGGCCCAUGGAGAUCCGUGCAGACGGCCUGGGCAUCCCGCAGCUCCUGGAGGCCGUGCUGAAGCUGCUGCCCCUGGACACCUAUGUGGAGAGUCCGGCUGCAGUCAUGGAGCUGGUGCCCAGCGACAAGGAGAGGGGCCUGCAGACCCCAGUGUGGACGGAGUACGAGUCCAUCCUACGCAGGGCCGGCUGUGUGGGUUCCCUCCAACCCUGCCAUUUUGUCUUCCAGAGAGCCCUGGCAAAGAUAGAGAGGUUUGAGUUUUAUGAACGGGCUAAGAAGGCUUUUGCUGUUGUGGCAACGGGGCUUGUUUGGUGCUGAGCUCAAGGGAGGCUGCUGGCUCCAGAGUGGCCCCCACGUACCCUUGACGAACCUUGAGUGGGAAAUCAGGCCUGGGGCCCUGGGGACUGGGCGGGGUGCCUGGUGCCCUGGGGACACCAAGGGCUGGAGUGGGGGCAGUGGCUGCCCUGGAGGCCUUGAGAGGGGUGGGGACUUCUGCCAUAGCCCCUGGGCUGUGGACACCAAGGGGGUUCUUCACCGGGGUCCAUUCCUUCCACCCGCAGGAGGGCAGGUGGCAGGGGCUGGCCUGGACGCUUCGGGAGGAACUGUCGGCUGGAGAGGCCUCGGUGUGGGCCAUGCCCUAUGCCUGUGGCAUAGGUGGCCUCCCGCUGAAAGCCUCACUUGCCCUGGCAGGCAGGGGAGGUAAAGGACACGAGGUCAUUUGGAGUCCAGUGCCAGGCAGAGGUGGGAUGCAGGGGGUUCCUGAAAGGGGGUGCCUGGGAGGCUUGCCCAUGGGAUGCUUGGACUGGUCCCCAAGGAUGGGGAAGAAUAACCACCAGCCACUGUCCGGACCCUCGUCUUGCUCCCCAGAACUUGCUGCAGUGACAGGUACAGGAAGAAGAUGGGGCAGGGCUGGAGUUUGAGGGACCAAGGGCAGGAGUGGGGAUGACAGGGGCUUCCCCCAGGGCCUGGGGCUGGUGUCCCCGGGGCUCGAGGGGGCAAGUCCCAGGGUUCCAGACCCCCACUCCAGACCGCAGGAGAACCUUGGGGGUGCAGGCAAGCCCACCCCGGCUGAGAUGUGGCUCCAAAUCUGGGGAAGGGACCCUGUCUGGGCUUGGCUGCAGACUUUGGGGUCCUGUCCGCCUGCUGCUCCCAGAUGGUAGCCAAGGCUUUCUCUGUGCUCACUAGUGGUCAGCCUUGGCCCCAGGGGCCUCGCACUUGCCUGGCCAAUCACUGCUCAUCUCUAGACCCGAUGGCCGCGUCGUGGCCUAACAUCAGCGGUGUACGAGCUGGUUGCACACACCCUCGCCCAUCCCCAGGCUCAGCCCCACAGAUGAGCCUCUGGGGUUAGUGUGCCCUCUCUAGCAUGUUAUAUAAAUGAAGCCAUAUAUGAGCAAACUAAGUAAAAUCACGAGAAAAAACAAAGUAAUGGGCAAAACAAAAUAAAAUCAAGAUAGCUUUAAAAAAAAAAAAAAAGCCACAAACACCAGCUUGGGCUGCCUAGGGCAAGACCCUCCUGCAACUCAGAGAUCCAGGGUCUUCUACCUGCCUGGGGCUCAGGGAGUGGGGAAGGAGUUGCCCAAAUCUCAGCCCUGAGCGUGUUGAUCCCUCAAUGCCCUCCUACCCCAUGUUCUUAUCAGGAUGACAGGGGAGGCUGCCAAGGGAGAAGCUGGCAGCCCAUCUCUGGCCCUUUUAGGACAGAACCUCAAAGGUCACUGGCCUCUCCAGCUCAUCCAUAAGCCAGGGUAACAGCUCUUACAUUGUGGGACACCGUGGGGCACCCUUGGGCAGUUACUCUCAGCCGUUGGUGUCCUGGGAGAGCGGGGAUUUGCUGGCGGUGCAAGGAGCUCUUCCACACCUGGGCAAACCCUCAGCCCCCUGAGUGGCCACACGAGGGCUGAACACGGCAGGAUGAGGGACGGGUGGCCUCUCUCCCUUGCUCCGUUCUGUCUUAGCUGCUGGAGCUGGCAAAUGUGUGUGGCUCAGCCCCGGGCUUGGCACCAGGUGCUUCUCUCUCACCAUAGGGAUGAGACUGCCACGCAGGAACCCCGCCCACAUUUGCAUGUGCCCAGGACACAUGCGGUGUGUGAGUGACUCCAGCAGCCUGGACCUGCGCUGCAGCAUUGGGCCUGCUGGGCCAGGAGGACAGGAUGGGCACCCAGAGUGGGAGCUGCACAGAACGUCAGGAGGGCAGAAAGGCCAUGUCCUGGGCCUGGGUCUACCCGCCCUCACCUGAGACCUGUGCACUUUCCACCUGAGCACAUGCACGUCCGUUCAGCUGGGCCCUGAGCCCCAGGCACUCGGCCACCCUCCUCCCCGACCCUGUCUCAGGCUCCUGCUGUAGGGAGCCCAGGGUGGGUUCUGUUUCUCAGCUGAGACUGGUCCCAGGGUGCCCUCUGGUCCCAUCCCCUAACUGCUGCCACACCCCUCACCAUCCCGGUAUACAAGGAGGAGGGCCUGGGGGUAGUGCAACCUUCUGGGAGCCAAGGGUCACCUGGGCCUUGUGCAGCCCUUGAUUCUCCUAGGCAGGGCAGGCUGGGCCCCGGUCAUCGGUCUUCUGGGGCAUGUGGCCUCCCACCUGUUUGCAGGGGUUGAUUGAUUGAUUGAUUGAUCGAUUGAGAUGGAGUCUUGCUCUGUCGCCCAGCCUGGAGUGCAAUGGCACGAUCUC